GGUUUCCGGUGCAGGUGGGGAAAAUGGCGGUGUCUACAGUGUUCUCGACUUCGUCGCUGAUGCUUGCUCUGUCAAGGCACAGCCUAUUGUCUCCUUUGCUCAGUGUGACAUCAUUCAGACGCUUCUACAGAGGUGACAGCCCAACAGAUUCCCAAAAGGACAUGAUUGAAAUCCCUUUGCCUCCAUGGCAGGAGAGAACUGAUGAAUCCAUAGAAACCAAAAGAGCCCGCCUGCUCUAUGAGAGCAGAAAGAGGGGAAUGUUGGAAAACUGCAUUCUUCUUAGUCUUUUUGCUAAAGAACAUCUGCAGCACAUGACAGAAAAGCAGCUGAACCUCUAUGACCGCCUGAUUAACGAGCCUAGUAAUGACUGGGAUAUUUACUACUGGGCCACAGAAGCUAAACCAGCCCCAGAAAUAUUUGAAAAUGAAGUCAUGGCCCUGCUGAGAGACUUUGCUAAAAACAAAAACAAAGAGCAGAGACUGCGUGCCCCAGAUCUUGAGUACCUCUUUGAAAAGCCACGUUGAGCUGUGCUCCACGGCCUGGCAUGGGGGUUCAGUCUGUGGAUGGUAACUACUUAUGAUGGACGUUAGCCUUGCUUCCGGCUUCUUAGAUGCCCAGCUGCCCUACCCCAGACCACUGGUCCUGCCUCAAGUGAUGGACAUAACCCUCUCCUAGGACAUACAUGUAAAUGCACAAUGUGACUCAUUCUCAUACUUUUUUGUUCAGCUCUGAGCCUCAAAAGUGAUUUGUCAGCAGCGCUGGCAUGCAGGCUUUGCCUGGCUGCUAUCUCUAGAGGCAAGUCUGCCACGAGAGGGCACUGCAGGCGAAGCAGUUGUGCUUGCUCAUUGCCUCAGCCCAAGUGUACUCAAAGAAAAGAGGCAGCCAGCUGUGCGUGCUGUAUGGAAAGCCUCCCGCCCUCCCUGCAGCUCCCCGCCCUCAGUGGCCCAGGGCUUUGUUGAAGUGGAACUCCCCACUUCCAACCUGGUAUGGCUCCUUCUGCGAAGGGAAGCUGAUCCCAGCCUCCUGAGCUGAAUCCUUCAAAGGCACAGCAGGCAGAAUGAGGGCCACAGGCAGGAGUGGUGUGGGCACACUGCUUAGGAGUCAACAUCUUCAUCAUUGGGCUUUCUUUAAAACGUGCACUUUGUAAUUUGAAAGAGAAUUAUUAAAGCAUACUGAAAAAAGGAAA